AUAGUUUUCGCCCGCGCUGCGCCGCCUGGUUGCUCCUCCCGUGCGGUGAGUCCCGAAGGCCCGGAGCCAAGUGGGUCUGGGCAAGCGGGGCCUUACCUAGGGAUACCACCGGACUUGGAUCGGAGCAGCCUUCAGGGGACGUGGCGCAGUCGAACAGAGCCACCAUGGGGACGACGGCCCCAGGGCCCAUUCACCUGCUGGAGCUAUGUGACCAGAAGCUCAUGGAGUUUCUCUGCAACAUGGAUAAUAAGGACUUGGUGUGGCUUGAGGAAAUCCAAGAGGAGGCCGAGCGCAUGUUCACCAGAGAAUUCAGCAAAGAGCCAGAGCUGAUGCCCAAAACACCUUCUCAGAAGAACCGACGGAAGAAGAGACGGAUUUCUUAUGUUCAGGAUGAAAACAGAGAUCCCAUCAGGAGAAGGUUAUCCCGCAGAAAGUCUCGGAGCAGCCAGCUGAGCUCCCGACGCCUCCGCAGCAAGGACAGUGUAGAGAAGCUGGCUACAGUGGUCGGGGAGAACGGCUCCGUCCUGCGGCGUGUGACCCGUGCUGCGGCUGCAGCUGCCGCGGCUACCAUGGCAUUGGCUGCACCUUCUUCACCCACCCCUGAGUCUCCCACGAUGCUGACUAAGAAGCCCGAGGAUAACCACACCCAGUGCCAGCUGGUGCCUGUGGUGGAGAUCGGCAUCAGUGAGCGCCAGAAUGCUGAGCAGCAUGUCACCCAGCUCAUGUCCACCGAGCCUCUGCCCCGCACUCUGUCCCCGACUCCAGCUUCAGCCACAGCUCCAACCUCCCAGGGCAUCCCGACAUCAGAUGAGGAAUCAACACCUAAGAAGUCGAAGGCCAGGAUACUGGAGUCCAUCACAGUGAGCUCCCUGAUGGCUACACCCCAGGACCCCAAGGGUCAAGGGGUCGGGACGGGGCGGUCUGCGUCUAAGCUCAGGAUUGCGCAGGUCUCCCCUGGCCCACGGGACUCGCCAGCCUUUCCAGAUUCUCCAUGGCGGGAGCGGGUGCUGGCUCCCAUCCUGCCGGAUAACUUCUCCACGCCCACGGGCUCUCGCACGGACUCUCAAUCGGUGCGGCACAGCCCGAUCGCCCCGUCUUCCCCGAGUCCCCAAGUCUUAGCCCAGAAGUACUCUCUGGUGGCCAAACAGGAAAGUGUUGUCCGCAGGGCGAGCAGAAGGCUUGCCAAGAAGACUGCCGAAGAGCCAGCUGCCUCUGGCCGCAUCAUCUGUCACAGUUACCUGGAGAGGCUCCUGAAUGUUGAGGUGCCCCAGAAAGUUGGUUCUGAGCAGAAGGAACCCCCCGAGGAGGCUGAGCCUGUGGCGGCAGCUGAGCCAGAGGUCCCUGAGAACAAUGGAAAUAACUCGUGGCCCCACAAUGACACGGAGAUUGCCAACAGCACACCCAACCCGAAGCCUGCAGCCAGCAGCCCGGAAACACCCUCUGCAGGGCAGCAAGAGGCCAAGACGGACCAAGCAGAUGGACCCAGAGAGCCACCGCAGAGUGCCAGGAGGAAGCGCAGCUACAAGCAGGCCGUGAGUGAGCUGGACGAGGAGCAGCACCUGGAGGAUGAGGAGCUGCAGCCCCCCAGGAGCAAGACCCCUUCCUCACCCUGCCCAGCCAGCAAGGUGGUACGGCCCCUCCGGACCUUUCUGCACACAGUGCAGAGGAACCAGAUGCUCAUGACCCCGACCUCAGCCCCACGCAGCGUCAUGAAGUCCUUUAUUAAGCGCAACACUCCCCUGCGCAUGGACCCCAAGUGCAGCUUCGUCGAGAAGGAGCGGCAGCGCCUGGAGAAUCUGCGGCGGAAGGAGGAGGCCGAGCAGCUGCGCAGGCAGAAGGUGGAGGAGGACAAGCGGCGGCGGCUGGAGGAGGUGAAGCUGAAGCGUGAGGAACGCCUCCGCAAGGUGCUGCAGGCCCGCGAGCGGGUGGAGCAGAUGAAGGAGGAGAAGAAGAAGCAGAUUGAGCAGAAGUUUGCUCAGAUCGACGAGAAGACUGAGAAGGCCAAGGAGGAGCGGCUGGCAGAGGAGAAGGCCAAGAAAAAGGCGGCGGCCAAGAAGAUGGAGGAGGUGGAAGCACGCAGGAAGCAGGAAGAGGAGGCACGUAGGCUCAGGUGGCUGCAGCAGGUGCGAGCACAGGAGGAGGAAGAGCGGCGGCACCAAGAGCUGCUGCAGAAGAAGAAGGAAGAGGAGCAGGAGCGGCUGCGGAAGGCGGCCGAGGCUAAGCGGCUGGCAGAGCAGCGGGAGCAGGAGCGGCGGGAGCAGGAGCGGCGCGAGCAGGAGCGGCGCGAGCAGGAGCGGCGGGAGCAGGAGCGGCGCGAGCAGGAGCGACAGCUGGCAGAGCAGGAGCGUCGGCGGGAGCAGGAGCGGCUCCAGGCCGAGAGGGAGCUGCAGGAGCGGGAGAAGGCCCUGCGGCUGCAGAAGGAGCAGCUGCAGAGGGAACUGGAGGAGAAGAAGAAGAAGGAAGAGCAGCAGCGUCUGGCUGAGCGGCAGCUGCAGGAGGAGCAAGAGAAGAAAGCCAAGGAGGCAGCAGGGGCCAGCAAGGCCCUGAAUGUGACUGUGGACGUGCAGGUGCCACCUGGGCCCCAGUGGAGAGGCUCUCAGUCUCCAGCUUGUACCUCAUAUCAGAUGACUCCGCAAGGGCACAGGGCCCCUCCCAAGAUCAACCCAGAUAACUACGGGAUGGAUCUGAAUAGCGACGACUCCACCGAUGAUGAGGCCCAUCCCCGGAAGCCCAUCCCCACCUGGGCCCGAGGCACCCCGCUCAGCCAGGCUAUCAUUCACCAGUACUACCACCCACCGAACCUUCUGGAGCUCUUUGGAACCAUUCUCCCACUGGACUUGGAGGAUAUCUUCAAGAAGAGCAAGCCCCGCUAUCACAAGCGCACCAGCUCUGCUGUCUGGAACUCACCGCCCCUGCAGGGCGCCAGGGUCCCCAGCAGCCUGGCCUACAGCCUGAAGAAGCACUGAGGCUGGCCUGCGGCCUUCUUGGCAGCCUCGCCUCCUGUCCAUGUCUAUCUGUCUGUCUGUCGGUCUCUGUCUUGGUCUGUUGCCCUCCUUCUUGGCAUGCCAUUGUGGAGGGCUUGGCCAGGUGUAUAUAAACGUCCUCUGUGCUGGGUGUUUCUGCUGCAGGUGGCAGGUGGCCCCAGGCCUGUUUGGAGGAUGGGCUGGGUGGGUGGGUGGGGAAGAAAUGGGCCCAGCCCCACAUGGCCUGCAGACAGUGCUCUGUAAAUAGUUGUUUUAAUUUAGCUGAAUGUUAGCAUUUUAGUCUUUGGCAUUUUAGCGUUUGGGAGGUAGAUUAAUAAAGUAUAUUCCUUCAAGCCUGCUGUUGAUACCAUGAAGACUGGGCGCCUCAGUCCCAGCCCUGUAGCUGUGUGUCUUGGGCCACCAGUGGCCUGCAGGACGAAGGUACUGUUCCAUCACCUGCGGUGUGCCUCAGGAUCACCAGGUGCAGGCCCCCACCCUCGGAGAUGCUGCUGCAGUGAGUGGUUCCACUGCCUGGAUAACCCUUGAGGAACACGUCAGUUACUGUCACGAUGGGGCAGGUGGAGCUCCUUCCUAUUUUUUGGGGUGCUCCCUGUUUGUAAAGGGGAGUUUGUUCAUUGGGAAAGACCUGGGUCUUGACACGGCCCUGCCACUUAGUCCCCUACCCUCUCCAUUCCCCAGGCUCCACCCGUGCUGCUCAGGUGCAAAUGGACUUGAGAGCAUCUAUGUGCUGGUGAAGCAUGAGGUCUGAGUAGAAAAGGGGUAUCCCUUGAGACCACCUUGGGACCAGUGCUUGCAAGCAGCGAGAUAUUUCCCCAGCAAAACCAGGCAGCUGCUAAUUAAAUGCUUAGAACCAAUGAAAGCUGGCUGUGGUCCUGCCUGUGAGCUGCCUACUGCUGCCUUCUGAAUGCAUAUAUCUGCUACUGUAGCCCCGGGUUGUCAAACUAUGGCCUGUGGGCCAAAUCCAGCCACAGUCGGUUCUUUAAAGUUUUAUCGAAACACAAGCAAUGGAAAUGCCCAUUUCCAUUGUUGUCUCCAGUUGCUCUGCUCCGAGGGCAGUGUUAAGUUGUGCAGCAGAGGCCCCUCCAUGCAAAGCUGAAUAUGUUUACUAUUUGAACUUUUUCAGAAGUUCUGCUUAAGGACAAAAUAAAGCCUAAAUCCAAGAACACUUUUAAAAA